AUGAGUCAUGUGCACAGACCACAGGAGGGAAGCAGCUUCCUAGAGAGAAAGGAGCAUCUCAGUGGGGCCUGGGAACAUGGGGUACAAGGGAGAAACAGGACCAGACUGGACGGCCACAUUGGGCAGGCGCACGCUUCCAUGCCAGGUCCUGGGGAAGCAGACAUGAAUGGCAGAGCUGCCUGAGAACUGGACAGACACGCGGGAGACGCUGCUGGAGGGGAUGCUGUUCAGCCUCAAGUACCUGGGCAUGACGCUAGUGGAGCAGCCCAAGGGUGAGGAGCUGUCGGCCGCCGCCAUCAAGAGGAUCGUGGCUACAGCUAAGGCCAGUGGGAAGAAGCUGCAGAAGGUGACUCUGAAGGUGUCGCCACGGGGAAUUAUCCUGACAGACAACCUCACCAACCAGCUCAUUGAGAACGUGUCCAUAUACAGGAUCUCCUAUUGCACAGCAGACAAGAUGCACGACAAGGUGUUUGCAUACAUCGCCCAGAGCCAGCACAACCAGAGCCUCGAGUGCCACGCCUUCCUCUGCACCAAGCGGAAGAUGGCACAGGCUGUUACCCUCACCGUAGCCCAGGCCUUCAAAGUCGCCUUUGAGUUUUGGCAGGUGUCCAAGGAAGAGAAAGAGAAGAGGGACAAAGCCAGCCAAGAGGGAGGGGACGUCCUGGGGGCCCGCCAAGACUGCACCCCCUCCUUGAAGAGCUUGGUCGCCACUGGGAACCUGCUGGACUUAGAGGAGACAGCUAAGGCCCCGCUGUCCACGGUCAGCGCCAACACCACCAACAUGGACGAGGUGCCGCGGCCACAAGCCUUGAGUGGCAGCAGUGUUGUCUGGGAGCUGGAUGAUGGCCUGGAUGAAGCGUUUUCGAGGGGCAGGGAGCUCACUGGGGAGGAAACCCCUUCCAGCGUUGUCCAGAGCUGUUAGAAAGUUCUUACUGUUGAGUCAAAAACUAUUCCUGGUGGCUGCUCUGCCGCAGUCUGAGGUGAGCGAAACACACUGCAGCUCAAGUUGAUUUCCUCCGACUUGAGGAGGCGUGGCCUUCAAAAAUGGGCUUUUUUUUUUUUUUACAGGCUUUGCUCCCUCCACAGGUCUGUGUUUAUGAACAGGGGAAGGGAGAAAGUGUUUAAUGAAGCUCGUGAAGCGUUCCAUAGCAGGGAAGGUCAGGCACAGUGAGGAGGUGUUUUGGUAUAGCCUUUGGUGGCAUUUCCCCGUUUUCCCAGGGGCCAUCCUUGUGGCCCCCUGCAGCUUGGGGACAUGCCACUGAGAAGGCUGUGGCUGAGGAGAGGCCUGGGCAGGUCAGGGUUCCGAGCCCUGGGUCCCCGUCUGUCAGGCCUCCCUUUCUCACUUGAGACCCUCAGCAGCCUCCUACAGCCCUCCCACAUCAGGGGCUUUGUUUGGGGUUGGAGUCAGCGAUUUUUGGUCCAGCGGGUGGGGACAGAGUCAGGGUCUUUGCCCUCCUGCCUCCUCCUUCCUCUUCCUUGCCUCCUUCUUGCCAGGGACUAGUGGAAACCCCUUGGUCCAGCCUGGGGCGAGGGCGACAGUGACACCUUCCCUGCCUCACUGGCUGACGACACCUGCCCUCUGAAGAAAAUCUUUUGUUUGCUUUCUCCACAUUAUUUUGAGCAUCAUGUGCCCUUUAUUAACAAUUUUGAAAAUCAGCAAAGCAUUAAACAGAAAGUAACACCAUCCUGUAAUCCCACAGCCCAGAGUUUUGGGCUUAAUUCAUGCUAAUCCUAUACAUAUACAUUAUUUUGCAUUGAUCAGCUCAUCGUAUUUGCAUUUUGGGAUCCUGAUUUUUCACUUAACAGCGAUGUGUCAGAAGCAUUGCUCCAGGCUGUUAAAAGCUCCUCGUAAACACCUCUUCCAUUGACUGCCUAACAUUCUCUUAAGGGAAGCUGCUAUAAUUUACUUGACUCUCCCCUAUUCUUUUGGACAUGUAGGUUGUCUCCCUUUGUAAAUUUAUUUUUCGAACAGCACGGUGUUGACACAGUUAUAGCCAAAGAAUCUUCCGUGUUCCCUCCCACAGCUUGUUCCCCACCCCACCCCCACCCCCGCUGCUCCCUUUACCAGCCCCUUCUCCUCUUUCCUGGGCAUGUCCUGACUGAGCUGGGGCACAGAGUGGGUGCUCUGGCCUCUCCCGGGGGUGGGUGCACCGCUGGCUGCCCCUGACUUUUCUGAGCUGUUUGACUCUCAAGGGGAGGUGCUUUGAUCUGAGGUUACUCCACCUCCCCUGCACCGGGGGCUUCCUUCUUGGGCCAUGUGCCCUGCUGUUCCCCACUGGUGCCCCCUCGCGUCUGACCCUGGGGCGCGCCAGCCCUCACCCAGGCUCUCGGCUCACACAGCUCUGCCUUCCAGGCUUGCCCAGUCUCGGACAAACCCUCAGGUCCUGGACACUGGCCUGACAGCCCAGGACAUGCAUUACGCCCAGUGCCUCUCGCCUGUCGACUGGGACAAGCCUGACAGCAGCGGCACAGAGCAGGAUGACCUCUUCAGCUUCUGAGGGCCCGGGGCCAGCCGGACACAAGCGGCCCUGACACGUGAUGGACCAAAGCCACCUGCUGCGGGGGAGCCAGUUCUGGGGCCCGCCUGCCACCUCUCCCAGCCCUCAGCAUUGUCAGCCUGAAGAUCAGAGCUGCAGCCAGUCAGGCAGGGGAGAGAUUUUUCUUUUAAGCCCUGCUCUUUCUCUGAGAACCAAAAGAUGCCUUGAAUAUUUAUUCAGUGACUUCUGGCUUAUGCUCAGAAGCCAGUCUGCGUCAGGCACGUCUCCUGCUGCGUGACAUGUGCAGUGCUGUAAUCGGCUCCCGCUUGCUCUCCUGGAGCAAGCUCUGCCCUGGCUGUGGGUAUCAGGACUGUGACCAAAGCAUUUCUAGUCCCUUCUCUCUUUCUAAGGACCCAAAUUUCCCUGGGGGCAUCCUGCUUCCUGAAAGCUGUUGGAUUUCAGUGAUUUUUCCCCCCACCCCCCAGCACAGGAGAGCACCCACAGCCGCAGAAGGGGAAUGUGUCCUCCUGCUCUGCUUCCUCAGGGCCCAGCAGGCGGGGGUUUGAGCCCUGGACCCCAGGCUCUUAGAGACUAAGGGGCAGCUCCUGACCAAAGACGAUACAGCUUGGCACUUUAAAGCAUUAACAGCAGGUGUGACCCUGAGGGCUCCUCCAUGGUGCUGCAUUGAGUCCAGCUUUCCUUCUGCCCUUCCUCCAGGAGAAGGGGCCCAAGGUCCCCGUGGAUGGUCUCCACCUGUGCUUGGAACCAGUGUAACUGGCUGCUCCCUGCUCCCAGGGACUGACACGGGGAUCAUCUCUGUGACCGCCCUCCGUCGGGCCCCUGCCUGCCUUCUCCCCUCCACGCAAGGCUGUGCUCUUCCUCUGGUUUCUGUGUGUCCGUUUGAGUGUCUGCGCCCCGCCUCCCCAUACUUCCUGGGAUGAUGUGUGAAACCUGACACCUAGAUUUAUUUGGAAAUAUUCUAUGACCACUUUACAGAUGAGGAAACAGGCCUCAAGCGUGGAGGGGUAGAGUGAAGAGUAGAACCCAGGUCUGAUGCCAAAGCUGCUUUCUUCUCUGCCUCCUCCUCACGCAACUCACACCUCCUUUUCUUCUAGCUUUGUUGUCCUCCCAGGAACCAAAAAACCCCAGCUAUUUUCUGACCAAAAUGUGUUUCAUAACAAACCAUCUGGUGCCUUUCCACACAGAACUGGCAGGAGCCUCGUGUCCUGCUAGCUGUCUCUCUUGUUGAUUUCCGUGAAAAUGCAAGUGUUUGAAGUCUGCUCAUUCCGAGGGUGAAACAAAAUCCAACCCUGUCAGAAUCAUGCUGUUCUCUUUGCUGACACUGUGACCCUGGGUCGGGACAGACCAGCAGCAAUCUGUCUUUAGAAUCGCUUUCCUUCCUCCCCUUUUGCCCCCGUGGGGCUCCCGGCAUCCUGAAAGCCAGCAAAGCCUCCAGCAUCUUUUCCAUCCUGAGGUGCCUCCCAGUGGCCUGGCUUGUCGGAGCAAGUUUCAUCAGCCCUAGGGAAAACACGGCCCUCCUGGGAACCUCCUUACCUGGAGUAACCGGACACCUUAGACGGAGGUGCCUGAGGGUGGGGUGGGAUUUGCAGGGUCAUUAUCAGAACAUGAGGAUAACUUCCUUGCCCCUGCUCUGUAGCCACCUCCUUGGCACCGGCCUCUAUUUGUCAUAAGGCGGCGUGGGCGAGGCCUGACACAGGCCAGCCUUGGCACGAGGGGGGCCAGGGGUUCUGAGAAGCGCUGCCCUGUGAGAGCCACGCUGGCCUUCGUCUCCAUCUCUGGUUGACGGGCUGUCCGUGUGCCUCCUGUGUGUCUGCAGACAAGUCUUGCUGUGCUUUAUUUGUGAAACUUUAAUGAGGAAAAAACAAAUAAUAAAUGUUCUCGUUUUGAAACUCAA